AGUGGGGCCUCGUUGUCACAGCUGACACAGAGCAGGGCCCAGGCCACCCGGCUUCUCUCUCCCUGUGGUUGUGAGCGCCGGGGUCCUUGGGCCGCCAUAGAGACAGGCCAGACAGGCUCUGGUCAUCUCAGCGGAUGCCUCCGAGCCGCCUUUCCCUUUUGAAGUCCCCAGCACUGCUCUGAAAUUUCAUUUACCGAUUAAAAAGCAAUUCCCAGGCCAUACUGACGACGUGCACGGUGUGAGUGACUGCGUCCUCUAGGCCUGAGUGGCAGCCACACAGCCUGGCCCUGGCAGUGGUGUCCUCCGCCUGGCUCCCUGAAUGUUCACCAGCUCCUGCGGGUUUUCCUCUCCUCAUGCUCCUGGGGGUGGGGCACCCAUCCUGCCCGUGUUGCCUCCUGCUCUAUGUUCUUGACGUGGGAUGGCGGCCAGGGACUCUGCCCUCGCUCAGUGCCUGCCCUUUAGGCUCUGUGACUGUGCACUUGGGAGUUCUGGGCUUCAGGGUCCCCUUAAGUCUCCUCAGGACAGCCGUGUGCGUGUCUCUGUGUGCACAGGAGCGACACAUGAGAAGGGAGUGUGGUCUCAGGGUGGGCGUGGACCCACAGUGCCCAGACCCUACUUGUCCUAGAAGGAGUGGCCUGGGAGGCCCCGCCUCCGCCCUCACUGGCCGCCGUUGGCUCCUCCCACUCGUGUCUUGACAGCUUAUUCUCGGGAUAUGUUUUGAUUUCUUCACUUCCUUUGUAGCUUAUUUUAAUAUUUUUGAUCUGCCGAAGAUGAGGGCAGAACAAAGAAUGUACUGGAACUCUCUUUGCAGGGCUGCUGCUCCCAGCAGGCCUUCGGGCUCUGCGGAGCCGGAGGGGGCUGAAUUGCCUUCCGGGUGUUUGUGGCCAGGCCAGGGUCGGGUCUCCUGCCUGAGUGGGCUGGGUCAGCGCCACUCUCCUACCCAUGGUGGGAGGUGGGAGAGGGCGGAGAUGUUCCCGGGUCCCAAACCAAGUGGGAGGCAGGGCUGCAGCUUUCUCCUUGGAAGCCUCCUGUGACAGCGGCUGUGCCUGAGCCUCUGGCCUGUCGGCAGUGCAGUGGCAGCAUGAGGGGCAGACAGUCUUCCUCCAGAUGCCCCCUCAUGUCACGGGGUUACAGAGGAAGCCUCCGCUUCUGUCCAGUGGCUGUCGGGCCCGGCCAGCUUCCUGCUGCUGUAUCUUGGAAGACCAUGUGGGCUGCAUGGGUGCUUGGCGAGUCUCCUCUUAGGGACCCUGGGGCUGCUAUCCUUGACAGGGGACCUUGUCUCACCUCCCCACUCGGUCCCACACUGGCUUUGUGACCUUGGACGAGUUGCUUAACCUCUCUGCCUCAGUGUAAACUGGGGACUACUGUUUAUUGAUCUUGGACUUUAUGUUUUGAGUGGUACAGGUGGGGCACAGAUGGGUCAUUGUGCUGCUGGGAGCACUUAGCCAAGACUGGAGCCUCUGAGCCUUCCCCACUCCCACCCCUCUUUCUUCUUUCCGGUCGGCUCGCCUCCUUCCUCGGGUUCUCUGAUAGCUGUAGGACUCCAUUGGACUACAUUUUUUUGUCAGUAUAGACAGCUGUCAGAGACGGAGACAAAAUGUGGCAGUUGGAGCUGCCGCUUGGCCUGCUGCCUGGGACGCGGCCCCUUGUCCCGCAGAACGUCAGCCAAGCGCUUUCCGUGCAGGCUGAUAACAGGGUGGUGCCGUGCUUCCCUUGGGCCGUGGCAGGAUCCUGCUCCAAGGGGGGGUCCUGCUCCGAGGGGGCCGGGGUUUCUGUUCCAACAGGGCUGGUGGGGGGGGUCCUGUUCCCAGAGGUCCGGGAUCCUGUUCUGAGGGGGCCAGGGUCCUGUUCUGGGCCGGGGGUCCUGCUCCGAGGGGGCCGGGCGUCCUGUUCCUAGGGGCGGUGGGCUGCCUGUGUGAGAGCUGUUCUUCACCUGCCACGUGCAGUCUGGGCAUUCUGGUGACUGGAGAAUUUGGGUUGUGUUACAGUGUUGUUGCUCUGUCCUGCAGAUGCCUGAAUUCCCAGGGGUCUUGCAGGUCCCCUUGCCCUUGCGCUGUGUGGGCUGGCGUGGGUCUCAGUGGGCUGUGGGUUGAGGGUCGCUUGGUUGGGAAGCUCUGCGCGCUUCCCAGUGGAGGGUCCGCGACGGGGGUUUUCUGAUCCCUCAUGCUGGCUUUUGACCCGUGUCACUGCAAGGCUGCCCCUGGCCCCAGGCAGCGUUUCUUCAGGCAGGUGCCCAGCCAGGUGGUCGGGCUUGAGACCUUUGAGUCUCGAGGUCUGUUCUGGGGAAUGACUGAGCUUGUGGAGGCCAGGAAGGGGUUGCUGGGCUUGGAGAGCCUCUGGGGAGGAGUUGUGUUUUGCUCUUUGCUGUUUUAAGCUGAAAUGAUCACAGGAAGGGACAGCAUCAAGAGUUUCUUUCUGGGACACCCCUCACUCAGCUCAGCGGCCGUGUGUGGGUUUGGGGCUGUGCUCUCCCAGACACCCUCAGGUCCGGGGAGCACUUCGGGGGCUAUCUGUCCCUUUGUCCACCAGCUUCCUUUGGAAAAAGUGUUUGCUGCAAGUGUUUUUCUCCAGCUUUUCGUGGGGUUCCCUGUAGUCUUGGGCCAUGCUCUGGGGUCAGGCUCCCGGCAGGCCCUGGUCCCCGUGCAGAAGGCCAGGGUCUGCGGGUUUGGGCUGGUCUGCCCCCCAGGUGAGGGUUCCGGAAAGACGGCCGGCUGCUGAGUCUUCUCAAGCAGGGGAAACAGCAGCUCGAGAGUGGUUCUUGACCUCUGCCCACCCCAGCUGGCUGUGCACGGACUGGGGAGGGCAUGGGCAGCUGCCCCCAGGUGGCUUCUGCAGGGAGCAGAGCUUAGUGGUCAUUUUCCCGGCAUGGUCUGUCAUCCGUCUGUCUGGGACCCCUCUGGGAGCUGGGCUGGGUCCCUCGCCUUCUGGGGCAGCAGGGUCACGGUGGGGGGGCUAGUCCUCUCUUUCAGCAUCUUGUUUCUCAGCCGUCCCUGCGGCUAUUUGUGCAAUGUCUGUCUGUCUGAGUCUCCGGGUGAGGGCAGACAGGAUAUGGUGCGAGGAAGUCUGGGGUAAGUGUGAGCCGAACCCCGCCCUGGAGUCUCUCGGGGUUGUGGGGCCACAGCCCCAGCUUAGGUUAGGCCUUCACUGCUGCUGGCAGGGCCUCCAGAGAGAAGGCGGUGGUUCCGGGGCCUGGGCCCUGACUGUCUGGCAGGAGGUGUCCACGCCGGCGGCCCGGCUCUCUGUGGCAAUAAUGUGUCUCUUUCUAAGGAUUGCGAAAGUUGAGGGAGGAUUUCUCCACUGGAAGAAUUAUGCAAGCUUCAACUGAAAUGUUUUUAAAAAGUUUCUUUGUUUUGAGUCAAAAUACAGAAGGUGAAUUAUUUCCCUAAUAUCUGGGAGAGCUGGAAAAGAAGGCCCCUGUCCUUAUUCUUCAGGGCUCUUCCCCUCCUGAGCAGUGGUCACCAGGCCAGGGUGUCAUGGAGGGGGGGCUGCCUGGGGACCAGCUCUUUACACCUGGCCUCCAGAGCGGGUGGUAGGGCGGCUCCUUCCUGCCCUGCCCUGGCUGUCACCCUCGUGGUCUGGAGCAGGGUUUUUUUUUGUUGUUAUUUUUUUUUUUUUUUGAGACAGGGUCUGUUUCUGUUGCCCAGGCUGGAGUGCAGUGGUGCGAUCUUGGCUCACUGCAGCCUCCGUCUCCUGGGUUCAAGCGAUUCUCCUGCCCCAGCCUCCUGGUAGCUGGGAUUACAGAUGUGUGCCACCACACCCAAGUAAUUUUUUUGUAUUUUUAGUAGAGAUGGGGUUUCACCAUGUUGGCCAGCCUGGUCUCGAACUCCUGACCUCAAGUUAUCUGCCCACCUUGGCCUCCCAGAGUGCUGGGAUUACAGGCAUAAGCCACUGUGCCUGGCCCCUGGAGUGGGUUCUGCCACGGAAGGCAUCCCCGGGGUCUGCGGGCUGGAGGGGUCGCCCCCACUGUGCCACCUGUUCUCUCGAGGCCUGGUUGCCCUCUGCAGACCAGGUGCCAUGCCAGGUGACCCUCAGGAAGCUCUGGCUCACCCCGGGGGCUGGGGGGCAUGAUAAGCGAUAGCUCUUAGGUGCUGCUGCUUUGUGAAUAUGAGAGAGUUCCAGAAGGGCCCCGCUUCCCAGAGCCUGCAUGUUGGUUUCACUGUGUGGUACUUGAUAUUUUUCCAGGCUGCCUUGCUGGGGUGGCCUCGAUGGGGGGCCCAGGGAGCCUCCAGCUCUGGGGACAUGCUGCCACAUGAGCCUGCUUAUUUACGAAAAUGAAGAACCAGGACUUGAGUGUGAAUUUUAAAUGAGAUUGUGGGGACAAUAGUAAAAUCCAGACUAGGACCAGAUGGACUGAGCACCUGCGUUGGCCAUGGCCCGGAGGUGGCGUGGUGGUGCCUGGCGCCUGUGGCCCUCAGCAUGUGUCCUGCCGGCCGCCUAGUAGGCCUUCGCUUGAAGUGCUUAUUCCUUUGAGUAAUGCUCCUGUCUUUUGUUUGGGGGGAAACAGAUAAAGGGGGCUUUGAGAGGCGUCUCGGCGUGAUCCUGGGAAACGGCCGAGAUUCUGUUCGGUGCUUGGUGUUCGUGUCUUCUCUGAUUUUACCUUUUUGACUCAUAAAGAUGGAAGGAGUGCUCUGCCUCGGUGCCUCUGCAGCUGCAGAUGCUGAAUCGGGGCGUUUAGGCCUGCCUCUUGGGCUGGCACACCUGGCGGCCUUGGUCAGGCCUUCUUGGGCUGCCUCUGCUGGGGUGCUUGUCUCACUGGCCGUGGGGGUUGUUGCCUGUGUGGUUGUGUUGCUGGCUUCAGGGGCUAGGGUUAGGGACGCCUGGUCACGUCUGGGUCCCCAGUUUGGGGGCCAGAUUCAAUAACUCACUGAAUGACUCAGUGGAACUCUGCAGGCACUGGCAGUCAAGGUUUAUUGGCAGGUCCAUUCUUUGGCUAGAAGGAGAAUGCUGUUUCUUUUCUCACUGUUUCACCAUUUUUUUUUUUGAGAUGGAGUCUUGCUCUGUUGCCCAGGCUGGAGUGCAGUGGCGUGAUCUCGGCUCACUGCAACCUCAGCCUCCCGGGUUCAAGCAAUUCCCCUGCCUCAGCCUCCUGAGCAGCUGGGACUACAGGUGCGUGCCACCACGCCUGGCUAAUUUUUUGUAUUUUAGUAGAGACGGGGUUUUACCAUGUUGGCCAGGAUGGUCUCCAUCUCCUGACCUCUUGAUCUGCCCACCUCGGCCUCCCAAAGUGUUGGGAUUACAGGCAUGAGCCAUUGCGCCUGGCCAUUGUUCCACCUUUGGAAGAAAUUGGUUCACCGUCUUCUGACCUGGGGGGCGCUUCUACCCUGGUUCCAUAUUGAGGGCUGGGAAGUUGCUGGAAUAUUAUUACCCUUGGCUGGUGAGGCUGAGUGCUGAUGCUCCUCCCAGCUCUCAGCCCUGCCUGGACCAACUGCGGCUUCUGCUGGAACGUCGGCGGCUGACUUAGAAAGAAACAGCUCCUGUUCUAGGCUUCCUGCAGGUCCCACGGUGCUGCUUGUUUCAGAGAAACGCAGCUCAGGCUGGCGGCCUCAGGUGGGCAUGGGUGGCAGGGGAUGCCAUCACCCAAAUCAGGGAUCUUUCUCUGUCCUGAGGGUUCCACCCCAGGACCCAGGGCACUAACUGGGUUCUUGUGUGGCCCUUCCCGACCAGACCUGACCCCUGAGCUGCGUGUGUGAGGUGAUGGUGACUCCACGACAGCUUGUGUGCCGUUAUGGGGGCACCUGAGGACUGGCUGACCUCACCGGGAAGUGCGUCAGGAGUGGGUGAGGGGUGGUGGGAGGGCAGGGAGCGCCCAGCAGGUGUCCAGCGGUGCUGGCGCUGCCUCUGUCUCUCUGUCCACGCCCUGUGUGUAUCUGGAGUGGCUUAGGUGCUCCCUGCGGUGCUCCUGGCUGCUGUGGUUCCUGAAGGCUGCGGCUGUGCCGGUGGUUUCCUUUGAUGUCAGUCUUCUUCUACAGGGGAAACCAUGUUGCCAGGAGAGCCAGGUGUCCGCUAAUUACGUUGUGUUGUUCUGCCCAGGAGUGAACCUGUAAGUGAUGAGAAUAAGAAGCGGCUGUCAGCCUGCAGACCCGCCCUCACCCUGUCCUGGUUGGGGUGCUGCCUGCUGGGAACCCCUGGUCCAGCUGUUGAGAGGAGGCUGACUGGGGGCACAGUUGUUGCAGAGUCUGAUGCAGGCUUUCUCUGCCGGGAAAGUAACAUGGAAACAUUGUUGCUUUUACUAUGGAGCAGAUGUAUCUUUGCCCAGAAACAGAAAUGCUCUUGGUUUCUUUUUUUGGAAAUAAGGCCCAUAGGCUGGGUCCUUCUUGCCCUGUUGAGGGAACGUGUCUGUCCUUAGCGUGGAGGCCAGUCUGGCCGGGUGCUGAGCUCGUCCUGCAGAACACGCGUGAACGCCUCAUCCCUGAGGGCCCCGGGAGGCUGGCGCCCUCUGUGGGAGGUCUGAGGUUGGCCCAUUUGACCCUAUCCAGGACGGGUUACUUAAGGAGUCCAACGGGCCUUGAGAGGCUGAUCACCCUCGUGUGGCGGGCGUCUCUCCCCGGUGCCCUCCCGCCUGGUGCUGUCAAGGGCUUCUCUGUGCCAGGCGCUGGGCUGUGGCAGCCCCAGGUCCCCGCCUGGUGUGGCUGCCCACGGUCCAGGCAGCUCCAGGGUGGGCAUCCUUGGCUCCCUCCCUCACCAGCUGGCCCUGGGAGGUCUGUCUGAGAGGAGUUAGGCCUCAUUGUCCGUGCUCAGAGAACCCGAGCCUUCCUUAGGAAGCAGUUUGUCCCCGUGCCUCCCUUCAGGAUCCUGUGGCCUGAGAAGCCUCUGCGUGGCAGUGGAUGGCAGCUCCAGCUGCCCGUGGCCCUCUUUUUUUAUGGUUUCCCAGAUGACUGGGCCAAGCUGGGCCUCUGCAUCCUAGGCAUGCUGUUCCCUGCGCUUCCCUGGAAGGUCGGCGGCCCUGCGUGGACCUACACGGUACCCAGGACAGGCCUGCCAUGGCACCGGUUGGGCCUCUGGGCACAGGGUGCUCUGCCUCCAUGGCCCUGACAGGCUCUGAUGCCUGAGGAUGGGGGCCGGGCACUCCCAGCCUUGAGACUUCCCUCUGCAGAGGUGGCACAAGCCCGGGGCCCCAGAGUGAGGGGACUCUUGCCUGCCUGGUGAGGGUGAGCGUGGGGUCUGGACUCUGACCCCUGGUCCAGGCGGGAGAGGAGCACACUGGACAGGGCAGCCGAGCCACCCUCUGCGGAGCUGUGGACACUGCGUGUGUGGUGCUGAAGGUGUACACGUCCACUGAGGCCACCUGCGCCGCUGCCUGUGUCCUGUGGGCUGGCACUCACCGAGUGAGAGCUGUGUGCAGAACCUCCGCUGUCAGCGGGCCAGGCCACACUGGGGAGGGAGGUAUUCCGUGUGCUUGCACUGAAGCCUGCCCCAGGCUGCCUUCUGGGUUAGGGAUACCCAGGACCUCCAUAGCUGGUGUGGCGUCUGUGAGAUCUCAGCUGCUGCUUCCCUGGACGCCCGUGUGGACCUGGAGGGGGGUGGGGACCCGGCCUGGCAUGGUCCCUGGCCACCUGCCUGGUGCUCCGGGUUGUGCCGUUGGCAGUGCCUUCGCUCUGCCUCACCUGCUGCCUCCGCCUUUCCUGGCUACAACCCUGUUGCCCAAACCAUUAAAAAAAUUAUACUACCAAGUUGAAUGAUAUGCAAAUGUAGUCAAUUAAGCGAGGGGAUUUUAAUUAGCAGUUUAAGUUCAUGUGUGAAGUGCCUUGCCUUAAUUACUUGACAGUUUUGUUGUAAAUUUGCUAAGUUUUUUUUUGCAGAACUAUCAAAACUGUGAUUUUUGUUAACAUUCUUGGAUGCGGUGAGUGGCGCCCAGCUUGCCUGACCCUAGUGGGUUUUGUCUUAAUUUAUAAAGCUCUUUAAACUGUGAAAACAAGGUAAACCCCCUGGGUUGCCUCUGUGUGGCUCUUCGAGUCAAGCCGGGCUCGAUGUCUUCCUUGUCACUGGCUGGGGUGGGGACCUGCCUCGUGCGUGGUCUUGAGCUCCCGUUGGGGGAACGGGAGAACCUUCAUCCCAUGUGGGUGUAGCCGUUGGCGGCACCUUUGUACGGGGACACACCCUGGACCUGAAUGGAGUCAGGAAGGGUUUCAACCUGGAUGGCCCGCGUGCCGGGGACCCGCAAGGUGUGCAGUGGCAAGGGCCGGUCCUGGUGGCGGGCUCCCUGGUGAUGCUGGUGGAUGGUUGUGCGUGGGCCUUGGGGUUCACAGUUCAGUUUGGGAGAGGCGAGAACCCCUCACUUUGAAGUCUUUCCUGGCCAACGGGAGGCUUCUCAGAGCAGCUUUCACGGCUCCGGGGCUGAGUGAGGCCUGUGUCUAGGCUCAUCCUGCCCUCCGGGGCGUCCCAGUGUGCCUGGGCAGUGGCGCAGCUGGCUCCUUCCACUGGGUUUAGGUGUGCUUCUGCUCCCCACUGCUGCUUCAGCUGCGUCCUUUGCGGGUCCCCGUAACUUCAGUGCCCCCACCCCUGUUCGGUUCCCUGACUGAGCUCGGCGCCUCUAGUGUAGAUGGGUUUUUAAUUUUCCCAGCUGAACGUCGUUAUUUGGAUUGUGAUUUCUUUGGUGUUUCAAUGGACUGUAGAUGAAGGAGGACCUGUUUUCUCUCAGGAGUGUCUGUGGGGUCUCUUGUCCUGGUUUGCUCAGUGAAGUGUGGCCCCAAGGGCUGAGGGAGGUGGCCAGGACCCCGCAGGGUGGCCCCCACCACAGAGGCUGCUGUCCUCCGGGUUCUUCUCCACUUUCUGGGACCUUGGCCGAGGAGGCCUCUGGGAGGGUGAAAUGGCCACAGGCCUGGAGAAGCGACACCGGUGGGAAGCCACCGGCAGAGAAGUCAGGGAGGAGGGAGUCCUGGGCCUGGAGGAACGUGGGAGGGGCAGGCGCCUCCUAGCAGCCUCAAGAAAUGUGGGCCAGGCAGGUCUGGCUACGGGCAGGAGUGUGUCUGGGACUCUGAACUGCCAGAAGCACUUGGCGGCAAGCCACAUGCUGUCACAAUGUUGCCUGGCCCCCAUGAGGAGGUCCCGUGGGUGGUGGCGGGUGGUGGCUGGUUGUGGGGCAAGGCUGCGGGACUGGGACCGCUGGCUUCCUGGGGCCAUCGAGGCUCCCAGAAGAAGAAAUCAAGAGGAUUUUAAGAAGCAGAGUUCUCUUUAGCCCGAAGUAACCAUACAGCAUUAACAAGAAAACUUGGAAUUCUUCGAAGUGAAGCUCUCUCUACUUGUUCGGAGGAUGGAGGACAGUUCUAGAUCCAGGAGAGCGGUGGCGCAGACACGGACUUCACCCUUGGUGGGAGGGGAGAAGCACAGCAUCCUGUUGUUCGUGAGUCAGGUCUCCUCUGAGCCUCCGGCCUCCAUAAGACCCAAAACAGAUGACACCUCUUCCCAGUCCCCCGCGCCUUCCGAAAAGGACAAGCCGUCCAGCUGGCUGCGGACCUUGGCCGGCUCUUCCAAUAAGAGCCUGGGCUGUGUUCACCCUCGCCAGCGCCUCUCUGCUUUCCGACCCUGGUCCCCCGCAGUGUCAGCGAGUGAGAAAGAGCUCUCCCCACACCUCCCGGCCCUCAUCCGAGACAGCUUCUACUCCUACAAGAGCUUUGAGACAGCCGUGGCGCCCAACGUGGCCCUCGCACCGCCGGCCCAGCAGAAGGUUGUGAGCAGCCCUCCGUGUGCCGCCGCCGUCUCCCGGGCCCCCGAGCCUCUCGCCACUUGCACCCAGCCUCGGAAGCGGAAGCUGACUGUGGACACCCCAGGAGCCCCAGAGACGCUGGCGCCCGUGGCUGCCCCAGAGGAGGACAAGGACUCGGAGGCGGAGGUGGAAGUUGAAAGCAGGGAGGAAUGUACGUUCACCUCCUCCUUGUCCUCGCUCUCUUCCCCGUCCUUUACCUCAUCCAGCUCCGCCAAGGACCUGGGCUCCCCGGGUGCGCGUGCCCUGCCCUCGGCCGUCCCUGAUGCUGCGGCCCCUGCCGACGCCCCCAGUGGGCUGGAGGCGGAGCUGGAGCACCUGCGGCAGGCACUGGAGGGCGGCCUGGACACCAAGGAAGCCAAAGAGAAGUUCCUGCAUGAGGUGGUCAAGAUGCGCGUGAAGCAGGAGGAGAAGCUCAGCGCAGCCCUGCAGGCCAAGCGCAGCCUCCACCAGGAGCUGGAGUUCCUACGCGUGGCCAAGAAGGAGAAGCUGCGGGAGGCCACGGAGGCCAAGCGUAACCUGCGGAAGGAGAUCGAGCGUCUCCGCGCCGAGAACGAGAAGAAGAUGAAAGAGGCCAACGAGUCACGGCUGCGCCUGAAGCGGGAGCUGGAGCAGGCGCGGCAGGCCCGGGUGUGCGACAAGGGCUGCGAGGCGGGCCGCCUGCGCGCCAAGUACUCGGCCCAGAUCGAAGACCUGCAGGUGAAGCUGCAGCACGCGGAGGCGGACCGGGAGCAGCUGCGGGCCGACCUGCUGCGGGAGCGCGAGGCCCGGGAGCACCUGGAGAAGGUGGUGAAGGAGCUGCAGGAACAGCUGUGGCCGCGGGCCCGCCCCGAGGCUGCGGGCAGCGAGGGCGCUGCGGAGCUGGAGCCGUAGAUUCCGUGCCUGCCGCCGCAGCGCCGCCGACAACGCGGGUGCAGGGGGGCGCGGCUGGGCGGUGCAGCUCCGCCCGGCUCCGCCCCUGCAGCCCACACAGCACAACGUCUUACCGUGCCUAUUACCAAGCGAGUGUUUGUAACCAUGUAGUUUUGGAACCCACUGCAAAAUUUUCUACUGGCCAAGUUCAAGUGAGUAAGCCGCGUCCCCCAACUACAGCUGGAGACGGGGCCAGCUCGGCGGCCUGCUGGUCCUCUGCUUGCUGGAACAUUCUAACAUUUACACUUUUGUUAUAAGCUAUUUAAAACCAGUAAGGAGACUUGAAAUUCAGAAAAUCAACACAUUUUUAAAUGACUAACUUCUAAAAGCCCCAACACAUGACGCCAUCUGAAGACCCGCAACGGAGUGGGGGUGGCGGCCGCCCCACCCUCCCCACCCGGGGAAGCCAUCACAGCUCAUCUGCCCGCGGCUGCGUGAGGACAGCAGGGGUUUUUCUUCAGAGUCUAUUUUUUCAGCGACAAGGACCCAGGUCUUCCUGCUGCUGCCAGGGAGAGCAGGGACAGUGCCGCGUGCGAGAUGAGCUCGAACACUGCCCGCCUUACUGCCGCCUACCCCGCCCGCCACGCCGCCGUCGAUGCCAGCGCUGUCCCCACGGGUACCAGGAAGUGCAGAGCCGCACAGGAGCUGCCCCGGAGCUGAGGGGACGGUCUUCGGCUCCUCUGCACCCCGUGAUUCUGCCCACGCUCCUCCACCACGAGGCACUGACCUGCGUCGGGUGGUGACCGUGGCUGGCGGUCACGCCCUCAGCCCCUCCGGGCACACGUGCCGCCUGACCGGGCGACCCUUUUCAGUUCGGCAAACGUCGCUCCCUUCAUUUUGGGACUGAGGCUGCAGCAUUGGAACAAAAGAGCAUUAUUUCAAUUUUUCUUUCUUUUUUUUUGUUCGUUCAUUUAAACGUAUAUUUAGAACUGCACUUUGUCCACAACCUUCCCUUCUCUUUCUAUUCCCCAGUGAACUGAGGUUUUUACCGAUUUAUAGAGCAGUCAAAUCCGAAGUGCUCGAGUGCUUAGAAACCCCCUCUGGUGCUUGGUUGAACAAGGGAAUCACAAGAAAACGAAAAUGCAAAAACUGAACUUCGGGGGUCGUUCUGUGCCUUCCAGCAUCUUGUACAGCAAAUCCUGACUCGUGUCUUUUUACCCCCAAGAUAUCUGUCUUCAGUAGCGACUGAAUCUGCCACUCUCAGAAUAAGUUCCUUGCAUUUAUUCCAAAUAAUCUCGUUUACUCUCACCUGUUUAUGCAAAUUGUAUAAGGUUUCUUAUGCCCAAGCUUGAAAAAUGAUUUCCCAGUAGACAAGAGGCGGCUACCUAUCCUACAGUUACGGUAUUUAUUUACAUAAGAAGAUCUUACAGGAGUUCUUUGCUUGAAUCCGUUCUAACACCCGCGGCAGCUGCACGCGCUCACAGAAGGUGGAGGUUACUUGCCCAGGUACAGACGACCUCGGGGCAGUGACGAGCAAAGACCAGAGACUGCUGAGCCCUCGCAUCUGGGUGGCGGAAUUGCCUGCGGGGUUUUGCCCUUGGUUUACUGAGGGGGGUCUUGGUUGCUGCUGAAGCCCCCCACCCCUUCUAAAGUGCAAUGCAAAAGGGACAUCAUGUAUAUGCAGCGUUUGUUUGGAAUUUUCUUUGCUUUUGUUUUCUUUGCGGUUGUUCUGUGUGCAUGGAUUCCACACCUCUGCCGUAGGUAGAUCCGUCAGCGGGCAUUAUUACCGUGUCUUGUAAAGGGUCGGUUUUGUUAUGCAACAUGCAGAAUGCUGUUUUUAGCCUUGUUUUACCAGAGUUGUUUUUUUUUUCAGUUAUUUCUUCAAGGGAAACUAAAUGAUUUAGUUGGAGCAAAGCUUUAAGUGUGUUGGCGUGCUUCUGUGUGGCUGUCCUGUGUCGCCAGGUCGAAGAUCACAGUGAGGUAGAGGCCCUGCCCCAUCCCCAGGGCCGCCAGGCUUGCUCCGUUUGCUUUGAGUUUUUAGACCCCAGAGGGAGAUGAGCUUUUCCAAGCUGUGUCUGGGCCAGAGCCUCUCCUUGCCCUUGCUCCAUCCCGACGGUCACCGUUGGGUCCACGCCUCCACCGCCCCAUCUUGCCCCAAACGGAAAGCGCUGUAUCUGCAGUGGCAGCCCUUCCCCACUUCGGCUCUGGGAGGGUCCAGCCAGUGUCACCUGGGCCCACCCUUUCCUGCAGCUGCCAGGCCCGUGCGGUCAGUGGGACCCGGACGUGGGCAGGCGAGCUCGGGACCCUCCCAGGCAGUUCCCACAGCUCUUGCCUCGGCUCACCAGGGUCACUUCCACUGUCAGGGGCCUGAGGGGGCAGCUGUGGCUGCAGGGCUGCUCUGGACUGAGGGGUCCCAGGCCCCGAGGGGUGCACGCCUGGCUCCCCUUGGCACAGGUGCGAGUCCGUUUCUUUUCAGCAGAAGGGGGAAGAGGUGUCCGCUGUGUGGGCUGCUGACUCCUCUGUGUGUGAGGCCCUUCAUCUAAGUGAUUGUGUAUUCAGUUUAAUUCUCAUUAUAUUUCUAUACUGAAAGAAGAUUUUUAACGAAGGGAAAAACAACAGCAAUAACAUUCAUAUCUCUGGAGCAGCUAACUCAUACACGUAAUGUCUGCUUUUCGUACAGAACUAGCCAAUGUAAAAACAGUUCACCUGUAAAUACUUUUUCCUUUUUCACCGUUGUAUUAUACAUGUAUAUGCUGGGUCCUUUUUCAGAAACUCUUUUCUUACCUGAGAGUUGUCUUGUUUUCUGGGCUGUUUUUAACUGAGGAAAAAAAAAAUGCUUUCCUGCCGGGGGGCAGGGGAGACGGAGAAACCCAUGUGCGUUUCCCAUGUGACCCCCUCCUCCCUGUGGGUCUGAGCCCCGGCCCCCCCCACCUCCUCCUCCCUGUGGGUCCGAACCCCGGCCCCCCCACCCCCUCCUCCCUGUGGGUCCGAACCCCGGCCCCCCCACCCCCUCCUCCCUGUGGGUCCGAUCCCCGGCCCCCCCCACCCCCUCCUCCCUGUGGGUCCGAACCCCGGCCCCCCCCCCACCCCCUCCUCCCUGUGGGUCCGAACCCCGGCCCCCCCACCCCUCCCUCAGCCCACCAGGGUCCAGGGAGAUGUUCGUUCUCGCUUUAAGUCAGGAGUCACAAAUGACUUUUUUUUUUCAAUUAAGGAAAAAGCUCCAUCUCUACCUUUAACAUCACCCAGACCCCCGCCCCUGCCCGUGCCCCACGCUGCUGCUAACGACAGUAUGAUGCUUACUCUGCUACUCGGAAACUAUUUUUAUGUAAUUAAUGUAUGCUUUCUUGUUUAUAAAUGCCUGAUUUAAAAAGAAAAGAGCUUGGCAUAUUUAUCUAUUUCGCUGUGUACCUGUUAGUCCUUCCCCGACCCCGAAACAGAUGACAUUGUACAAUAAAGGACUUUGAGAGGA